GCUGUGAGGCUCGGAGUCGCCGGAGGAGCCAGUAUCUGUGUCGCCGCCGCCCGCGGCGUCCCCGGUUUGGUGUUGCGGCGCCCACCUUCGGGAGGAUCAGGCUGCUUCUGAUGCUUGGAAGAUAUCCUCUCAGCCACAAAGAUGGUAAUAAAUCUUUGCCUCCCACAGUUCAGACCAAGAAUUCACUGCAACAAGAUAUCAGCUGAUGGUUACGAAGUAGAAAAUCUCAUCUCUGAAGAUCUCACAAAGAGAAGUCAUGGUUUCAGGACAGAGUAUUUCAUUAAGCCACCAGUCUAUGUGACAGUUUCAUUUCCCUUUAAUGUGGAAAUCUGUAGGAUCAACAUAGACCUCACAGCUGGGGGAGGUCAGAACGUCACUGGCCUGGAAAUGUACACAUCUGCCUCAUCUAGCAGAGUGUCUUGGAAUACGCCCCAGUGCCGGACCCUGGGCCCAGCUGAGCCAUCUGUCCCAGACAAGGAGGCGUUCACCUUGGUAGGCAAAGUCUUACUGAAAAACCAGAGCCAAGUGGUGUUUAGCCACAGGGGCUUCAAGGCCAGGCCCCCUUUUGGCGCGAUGGAAGCCACACUCCCCUCCCCUGCUGUUGUGGCCCAGGAGCUCUGGAAUAAAGGGGCUCUUUCCCUUAGCCACGUGGCCCACUUAAGGAUCUGUAUCACCCAUGUGACAGGCGGCGGUAUCCCUUGUAUCAAGCGGUUGGAAGUGUGGGGUCAGCCGGCCAAGACCUGCUCCCAGGAAGUGAUAGACAGCAUCCUGCUGGUCACCUCAGAGAACCUGCCUCAGGAUGUGGCUCUGCAGGCUCCAGCCUUGCCCAUGGAAAGUGACUGUGACCCUGGGGACCAGCCUGAGAGCCAGCAGGCUCCCUCCAGCCUGCAGAAGCUGGCCGAGAUCAUUCAGGAUGUGCCUGAGGAGUUCCUGGAUCCCAUCACCCUGGAGAUCAUGCCUUGUCCCAUGCUGCUGCCCUCAGGCAAGGUCAUCGACCAGAGCACACUGGAGAAGUGUAACCGCAGUGAAGCCACAUGGGGCCGAGUGCCCAGUGACCCUUUCACGGGGGUAGCUUUUACUCCGCACUCUCAGCCCCUGCCUCACCCCUCCCUCAAGGCCCGGAUUGACCAUUUCCUGCUCCAGCACUCCAUCCCUGGCUGCCACCUGCUUGGGAGAGCACAGACGGCAUUGGCAGUGAUCCCUUCUUCCAUUGUUCUGCCCUCUCAGAAAAGGAAGAUAGAGCAGGCUGAACAUGUCCCAGACAGUAACUUUGGUGUAAAUGCUUCCUGUUUUUCUGCCACAAGCCCUUUGGUCUUACCCACUACCUCAGAGCACACUGCUAAGAAAAUGAAAGCCACCAAUGAGCCCAGCCUGACACAUAUGGACUGCUCGACAGGUCCACUGUCCCACGAGCAGAAGCUGUCACAAAGCUUGGAAAUUGCCUUGGCAUCCACCCUUGGCUCUAUGCCCUCCUUCACGGCACGGCUGACCAGGGGACAGCUCCAGCACCUUGGCACAAGAGGGAGCAACACUUCCUGGAGGCCUGGCACCGGCUCGGAGCAGCCUGGGAGCAUCCUGGGCCCCGAAUGUGCCUCCUGCAAAAGAGUAUUUUCUCCCUACUUCAAAAAGGAGCCGGUGUACCAGCUGCCCUGCGGCCACCUCCUGUGCCGACCCUGCCUGGGUGAGAAGCAACGCUCCCUGCCCAUGACGUGCACAGCCUGCCAGCGGCCGGUUGCUAGCCAAGACGUGCUGCGGGUCCACUUCUGAGUGACUGACCUCCACUGGAGGAGACCCAUUGCUGGGAGGAGCUGAGGGGGAACAGGAGCAGGGCCACAGCACCCCUGAGGUCUGGCCAGGCCCCAGGCACAGAGCUGCCUGCUCCCUCCCGGGGCUCUUCUUCAUCACCUCACGGUAUAGCACAUUGCUUCUGCGCUGGUGGCAAUAGGGCAACAAAGCCAUAGGCCAGAGGGCGGGGGGAUGUCCCUGCCUCCCUGCCACCCCCCCUGCCUGAGCCCAGGACCCACUGGAGCCAGCCCCACCCUAGGCAGGAAGACCCCUGCUGAGGGCCCCCCCGUGCAGUCCGCAUACCCCCCUGUCCAGCAGGGCACUGUGGGUGGCUCACCCUAGAUUGUGGCCCAGAUCUCAGGAGUCUCUGCCUUCAGGGUCAUCCAAAAGUGGACCUUGGGAGCAGUGGGGGUGUCUGUGGAGUGCAUGACUCAGCCCCCCGACUCGCAGCCUUAAUAAAGCGAUGGUUGACGUCUGCUGUGGGUUUCCUCCUGGUGGAGUGCCUGUCUGUGUCACACACUCCUGUCGCCCACCUGCACCCACACAAGUGGAGCUCACAGGGUAGCUGUGUGCAGUCACUGCAGCUUGCCAGGCUGUCAUUCCUGUCGAUGACCUGAAAGGACACAAACUGGAAUUUUCAGGUCUGUCCCCUGCAUGGGGACUCAGAACCCAGGUUUGCAGGUGGGCAUACGUGGUGGGAGGGUGGAGGGCUCCCUCUGGCCAGUGCCAGCUGUGCUCAGCUGGCUUCAGAAACUGCUCCCUGAGGGGGAGCGCAGCGUUUCCUCAUGCAGUUGGUUUCAGGAAAAAUACUUGUUUAUAGGCUGCAUCCUUUUUUCAGCCCAACAUUUAGCUUUAUGGAGUGCCAAAGGGAAAAUAUAUCCAUAUCCCUACAACUUGGUACUCUAUCAGAUUCCAGCCACUAGAAGAACCUCAGUGAGAAAACACACCCGCCUUUCCCUGUUCCCUUCUAAGCACGUUUGGGAAGGAACAGCCUAAAGAUGCUUUGUAAAGCUGUAUUUUACCCUUGAGCUUAGCCGCGGGUCCCUGUGAACCGGCACAUUCCUUUCCUUUAGGCCGUCCAGAGCUCUAGUCCACACCCAAUACUUUAGAGAUCUGGGUUUGGGGUUAGUUGCUUUUUUUUUUUUUUUUUUAAUUGAGACAGGGUUGGUCUCUGUUGCCCAAGCUUGAGGGCAGUGGUGCAAUCAUAACUCAUUGCAGCCUCGAACUCCUGGGCUUAAGGGAUCCUUCUACCUCAGCCUCCCAGGUAGCAGGAACUAUAGGCAUGUGCCACCAUGCCCAGCUAAUUUUUUUAUUUUUUGUAGAGACAAGGUCUUGCUAUGUUGUCCAGACUGGUCUCAAACUCCUGGGCUCAAGCGAUCCUCCCAAAGUGCUUGGAUUGCAGGCAUGAGCCACUUCGCCUAGCCAAGCCUGCAUUUUUUUGAGUUCCUACAUCAUUUGUCCACAAAGAUGGCUUCAGAGAGGUGGUCACAUGCUUUGCUCUGCUUCCUCUUGGCACUGACCUUGAUGCAGCCUUCACAUGAGAUUUGAGGGUCCGCAUGGAUGGCCUGUGCCGCCCUCGCUGGCGAGGCUCCUGUGUGCCCCUGGCUUUCUGGGUCUGUGCCUCUCCAGAAUCUUGUCUUACCCUCCGGUGUGCUUGUGUUCUUAGAAAAGCCCCAGCAUGGCCGGGCAUGGUGGCUCAUGCCUAUUAUCCCAGCACUUUGGGAGGCCAAGGUGGGUGGAUCACUUGAGGUCAAGAGUUCGAGACCAGCCUGGCCAACAUGGCAAAACCCCAUCUCUACUAAAAAUACAAAAAUUAGCUGGGCAUGGUGGUGUGUGCCUGUAAUGCCAGCUACUCAGGAGGCUGAGGCAUGAGAAUCGCUUGAACCGGGGAGGCAGAGGUUGCAGUGAGCCGAGAUCUCACCACUGUACUCCAGCCUGGGCGACGGAGUGAGACUCCCUCUCAAAAAAAGAAAAAAGCCCCAGCAUGUAGCAAAAGCAUUUCUUGGUGAGUGUGGGGGCUGGUGAUUCCCACCUUCACCCUGUCAUGGUCUCAGGGAACAGCCUGCUUCCCACCAGCAGCUUGACACCCACAGUGUGCUCUGGCUGCUGGGAGCCCAUCUCUCGGAGAAACCCUGUCCACCCAACCCCGAGAGCCCUAGCGUGCAGUCAGCGUCAGCACGGCGCUCCCAGAUGAGGGCCGGACUGCCUCCCCUUAAGCAGCUGUGUUGGAGGUACUGCCCAGACCGCUGCAGGUCCCUGGGGAUCUGCAUUUCUAACAGGCUCCUGCCCCCAAGACUGCUCUGGUGGAAAAUCCAGCCUGGGAGCCCCUGGAGUGGCAGGCCCUGUCCUGGGUACAGGUGGAGCCACCCCCAGGAGUUGCGUGUGUUUUUCUUAAUUGAAAGACUUCCCCCAAAAGGAAGUGGUCUUUUCACUACCCUUGCCAGAAACAUGCUAGGCACCACUGGGCUCUGUUUCUGUCCCCUAGAAAAUGGGAAUAAAAUUUCUUUUGCUGUCA